GAUGCAGCAGUCUCGGCCCUGGCUGCUCUAUGCAGUGAAUAUUACAUGAAGGAGCCGGGGGAGGCAGAUCCCGCAAUUCAGGAGGAGCUGAUCACGCAGUACCUGGCUGAGCUUCGGAACCCCGAGGAGAUGACUCGCUGUGGCUUCUCGUUGGCCUUGGGCGCCCUUCCAGGCUUCCUUCUGAAAGGCCGGCUCCAGCAGGUUCUCACAGGUUUAAGAGCAGUUACCCACACUUCCCCCGAGGACGUAAGUUUUGCUGAGUCCAGGAGAGACGGCUUGAAGGCCAUUGCGAGGAUUUGCCAGACUGUUGGUGUGAAAGCAGGAGCCCCAGACGAAGCUGUGUGCGGAGAGAAUGUUUCCCAGAUUUACUGUGCGCUGCUGGGCUGCAUGGACGACUACACCACGGACAGCAGAGGGGACGUGGGCACCUGGGUCCGCAAGGCCGCCAUGACCAGUCUGAUGGAUCUGACACUUCUGCUGGCUCGGAGCCAGCCUGAGCUGAUCGAGGCCCAUACCUGUGAGCGCAUCAUGUGCUGUGUGGCCCAGCAGGCCAGUGAGAAGAUUGACCGUUUCCGUGCUCACGCCGCCAGCGUGUUCCUGACGCUCCUGCACUUUGACAGCCCUCCCAUCCCCCACGUGCCCCACCGAGGAGAACUGGAAAAGCUGUUUCCCAGGUCCGACGUGGCCUCCGUGAACUGGAGUGCACCUUCCCAGGCCUUCCCACGCAUCACCCAGCUCCUUGGGCUGCCCACCUACCGCUACCACGUCCUGCUGGGGCUAGUCGUGUCCCUGGGCGGCUUGACGGAGUCGACGAUCCGGCACUCCACCCAGAGCCUCUUUGAGUACAUGAAGGGCAUUCAGAGCGACCCGCAGGCCCUGGGCAGCUUCAGCGGGACCCUUCUGCAGAUCUUUGAGGACAACCUUCUGAAUGAGAGGGUGUCCGUGCCGCUGCUGAAGACGCUGGACCACGUGCUCACCCACGGCUGCUUCGACAUCUUCACCACGGAGGAGGACCACCCCUUUGCUGUGAAGUUGCUUGCGCUCUGUAAGAAAGAAAUCAAGAAUUCAAAAGAUAUCCAGAAGCUCCUGUCAGGCAUCGCAGUGUUCUGCGGGAUGGUGCAGUUCCCCGGCGACGUGAGGAGGCAGGCCCUCCUGCAGCUGUGUCUGCUCCUCUGCCACCGUUUCCCGCUGAUCCGGAAGACCACGGCCAGCCAGGUGUACGAGACAUUGCUCACCUACAGUGACGUCGUGGGCGCGGAUGUGCUGGACGAGGUGGUGACUGUGCUCAGUGACACUGCGUGGGACGCGGAGCUUGCAGUGGUGAGAGAGCAGCGCAACCGUCUGUGUGACCUUCUGGGCGUACCCAGGCCCCAGCUGGUGCCCCAGCCUGGUGCCUGCUGAAGCCAGUCCUGGAGCCCAUACCUCACCCCUGCCUGGUGAGGAUGUCUUGUUCCUGAGGGAGGCCGGUGUGGAAAGCCUCGCACAGUGGUGCCUCCAGCUGUUGAAGGGUAGCGCUGGCCCUUGGAGGCUGGCACUAGCUGACAGCUUUUCCUCUCUGCACCUGCGCUCUGGUGACUUGGGGUGGACGCCUCUGCCUUCACUUGAACACAAAUGUGCUUCCUAUAAAAUCAUGUACCAAGAAGUUCCUGCCUUUUGUCUCUGAGCCUGAUGUGUGUAGGGGUGAUGGAAAGGCUCACUGCCCAGGGGUCAGCCAGAGGGGAGGUGGGCUGCACUCCUCCUGCCUGGAGACCAGGCCCCCUUCUUGCCUGGUGCUGUCCCUGCUGUGGGAGACGUCUGGCCACAGGCAGUGCCCCACCCAGUCUUGGAGAGAGAUGAAUGUUAAAUCAGAGGUUCAAAUGCUAGAGAACUGAGAAGCCCUGGUGGCAGGCAUGGUCUGGAGUGCUGGGCAGAUGCUGUUUCUGGGCCCGUCUGCCUGGUGGGGGUGCUGUCCUCCCCCCUGUGCACACGUGAGCAUCGUGCAUGUGGCCCCUCUGCAGUGCAGGAGUCACUGAUUGAUGGGUGUGCCGACCAGCAGCUUCACAAAUGUCUGCUGCAAGGGGAAUCGUCAGAGUCCAAUGUGUGCCUCUACAGUAAUGUGGGAAAUAAAUACCAUUCUUGAAAUAAUUACACUGUCUUAGGAGAGCCUGGGCAGAGUCCACACUUGGGUUUUUAGGCAAAGGGCAGGAGGCUACCUUUGUCUCUGUGUCUGAGCUCGUGCUGAUCCAUCCCAAAGCUGGUGAGGGGAACGUGUAUAAAAAUUUCACUGUGGUAGCAACCCACACCCAUCUCUGGGACCUGUGCUGUGCUCAUAGGGCUUGAGGUGCAGAACCACGGCCAGCAGCACCAAAGCAGCCCCAGGUGUGGCCACUCAGAGGCCCAAGGGCUUGGGUGAGCAACCCUUUCCCUAUGUGAGGAGCCCAGGGGUGCCAUGUGCGUGGUGUAGAUUAGGGUGGCUCCCUGGCCUGCUCUCAGGUGGGGAUGGGGCCUGGACACAGGAACAUGGGCAGGCCAAGAACUGGGAGGUGCCACCGCAUCUGUGAGGCUUGUGAGGUCACCAGGACCACAAGACCAGGACUGUGACAGUCCGUGCUGUGUGUUUAGCAGACAGCUCUUCACGGGAUGUGUGUGACGACCUGGCCACACAGGAGUGUGGGGUUAACACACUACUGUUGUUGUGUUUGACCUGGUGGCCAAUGGUCUUUAUACCCUAAAAGAGCCUUGGGUUACAUUUUUACGAGAUUUAAAUAUUUUAUUCCAACCUGUGUAAUAGGGGUCUCCUCCUCCUUGAACUGUCCCGAUUGGCUGGGGUCACGUGGUGAGGGUCCUGGGUGACCAGGCCUAGCCUUGGCCACAUGAGUCCACACAGUGGAAAAGGCUUGGCUCCUGUGGUCGGCACACAUGAGACUCUGGUUGCGCCUGCUGGGUGUGGAACAGGCGCACCAUCGCCAUGCCUGCAGCUCACAAAGCUCCUGCUGGCCUGGGAUGCACUGAGGAUGGAAGGAACAAGUGGCUUCUGAGAAAAACAUGAUGAACUGUUCUUAGUGCAAUUAAAAGAAGAUUCCAGAUAAAUGGCAUUUUAAGACAUGGAGGCAGGUCGAUUACCCACCCAGACCCAUCAGUGACACUAUGUGGCAAAGCAGUUCUUCUUUUAAUGUCGGUCUAACUUAGCAACCCGAGGAAAGUGGAUCACUCCACUGGCCACUGCCUCUUUCCCACUGGAUCCCAUCCAUCACUGGGGCACUUGUGCUCACCAGACACCUGGUGGCCUGGAAAGCCCUCUUUCAGCAGCCGUUUCUGGAGCCCACCAGGGUCCAGGUGAUAGAGUUUGGCAAGGAACCCCUUGCUCACAUGAUAGCUGGGGCAGACAAUAGCAAAUGAACAAGCAAGCACCAUCAAGGCAGGCAACACUGAGUGCUAUGAACAAAGAUAAAGUGGGCAAUGGAAUGGCAUGUUGGGUGUUGACUCCGAGAAGGUGUUCAGAAAACCUCUCUGAAGGGGCAGCAUUUGGGCAGAGGUCCAGACUGUGUCCAAUGGCAGAAAAGAGAAUGCUUGUGGUCCCAGAAGUGGAGCAAGCUUUGUGAGUUUAGAGAGCAGCAAGAAGCCAGUAUCCCUGGGACCGGGGAGCUGAUGUGGGAUUUGUGUACCCACAAACACGUUCUAGGUGCUAACCAGAAACCCUCCAUGUGAGAGCAGAGACCUUGGAGAUCCUGAGGGUUUCUGCUGAGCCCUGGAAUCUAGUCACGCUAUUUUGAUAGCAGAAUGGAUGAGAGAAUUUAAGGCCCAGGGCCAGAUCUAAUGGACCGCUAUAUAAAGCUGGGACCCUAAAUAAGUCUUUUUCAAAGGAACAGCAGCAAGACUCUUAUCUCAAUCUAUCUCCCCUGAAGUGGCCUGAAUUAAUACUACCUGUAUGAUCCCCAAAACUCCUAAAGUGGAAAAUUUGAUUGACUUGGCCCUGACCAGUGGUAUUCCCAGACAAGGGCAGAAGAUGCAAAUACAAAACCUCUCUGGUAGAAUGUAGGCUAUAAUAUGAGUACAUUUUUGAAAAGGGCUAGAAAUGAUCAAGAAGAGAUUAGAAAAAAACAGAGCCCCUAGAAAUGUAAGAAGUGAAAUGAAAAGCUCAAUGGAUAGCUUAGACACAGCUGAAGAGAGAAUUAGAAAACUGGAAGAUCUGAAAACAUUAUCCAGAGAACUGGAAGAUAUAACAGCAACAUCAAGAGACAUUGAAGAAUGUCUAACCUUUGGGUAAUUGGGGUCUCAGAAUGAAAUGAAGUGAUGCAGAUAUUCCAUACUGACAUGCAACAGUCCCCAGAUACAGAAGCCUAACAGUCUCACAUUUAGACCUGCCACAGUGAAACUGCAGAACUGUAAGAAGGACAGAGUGAUAUAAACGACUACCAAUUUCCCAGCAGCAGCACUGGAGUUGAGCAGUGAGUAGACCAAGGUCUUCAUUAUGCUGAGAGAAAAUAGCUGUCAAGUUGCUUGAAUUGUGCCCACAGCAUAACAUUAAAGAAGAGAACACAAUUAAGUCAUUUAGAUAAAAAUAUGCCAUUCUUAUCUGUUUGGUUUUUUAAUCUUGGCUUAAUAUUUGGGGUUGAGUCAUUUGUUUUGAGAGCUGUCCUGUUUAUUGCAGGGUGUUCAGCAACAUCCCAGAUGGAAGCAGCAUCCCCCUACCCAGCUGUGACAAAAAGAAAAAAAAAUGUCUCCAGACACUGCCAAAUAUCUUCUGGGGGUGCCCCUGGUUGAGAACCACUGCUUUAGUGGAUAAACUUUAGGCAGGAGGGAAAUGAUCGCAGUUGGAUAGUUGGAGGAAUGUGGAGCAAGGGAAGCAAUAAACUGUGACCAUAAAAACAUA